CUCUCCAAACUAAGGGUCUCUCAGCAGAUGGCCGGGUUUAGAGCUGUACGAAGACACACAGCUAAUGAAAAAUUGUGGAAUUCUCAGAGCCCGUGAAGCCUAGCCCACGGAUGCGAGGUGACCAGCAAUGGCAGCAUCGGGAGGGACCCGCCAGCGGAGACCCAGCCUCAGAACCCACCGGCCCAGCCGGCACCCAAUGCCUGGCAGGUCAUCAAAGGUGUGCUGUUUAGGAUCUUCAUCAUCUGGGCCAUCAGCAGUUGGUUCCGCCGAGGGCCGGCCCCUCAGGACCAGGCGGGCCCCGGAGGAGCUCCACGCGUCGCCAGCCGCAACCUGUUCCCCAAAGACACUUUAAUGAACCUGCAUGUGUACAUCUCAGAGCACGAGCACUUUACAGACUUCAACGCCACGUCGGCACUCUUCUGGGAACAGCACGAUCUUGUGUAUGGCGACUGGACUAGCGGCGAGAACUCAGACGGCUGCUACGAGCACUUUGCUGAGCUCGAUAUCCCACAGAGCGUCCAGCAGAACGGCUCCAUCUACAUCCACGUUUACUUCACCAAGAGUGGCUUCCACCCAGACCCCCGGCAGAAGGCCCUGUACCGCCGGCUUGCCACAGUCCACAUGUCCCGGAUGAUCAACAAAUACAAGCGCAGACGAUUUCAGAAAACCAAGAACCUGCUGACAGGAGAGACAGAAGCGGACCCAGAAAUGAUCAAGAGGGCUGAGGACUAUGGGCCUGUGGAGGUGAUCUCCCAUUGGCACCCCAACAUCACCAUCAACAUCGUGGACGACCACACGCCGUGGGUGAAGGGCAGUGUGCCCCCUCCCCUGGAUCAAUAUGUGAAGUUCGACGCCGUGAGCGGUGACUACUAUCCCAUCAUCUACUUCAAUGACUACUGGAACCUGCAGAAGGACUACUACCCCAUCAACGAGAGCCUGGCCAGCCUGCCGCUCCGCGUCUCCUUCUGCCCACUCUCGCUUUGGCGCUGGCAGCUCUAUGCUGCCCAGAGCACCAAGUCGCCCUGGAACUUCCUGGGUGAUGAGUUGUACGAGCAGUCAGAUGAGGAGCAGGACUCGGUGAAGGUGGCCCUGCUGGAGACCAACCCCUACCUGCUGGCGCUCACCAUCAUCGUGUCUAUCGUUCACAGUGUCUUCGAGUUCCUGGCCUUCAAGAAUGAUAUCCAGUUCUGGAACAGCCGGCAGUCCCUGGAGGGCCUGUCCGUGCGCUCCGUCUUCUUCGGCGUUUUCCAGUCAUUCGUGGUCCUCCUCUACAUCCUGGACAACGAGACCAACUUCGUGGUCCAGGUCAGCGUCUUCAUUGGGGUCCUCAUCGACCUCUGGAAGAUCACCAAGGUCAUGGACGUCCGGCUGGACCGAGAGCACAGGGUGGCAGGAAUCUUCCCCCGCCUAUCCUUCAAGGACAAGUCCACGUAUAUCGAGUCCUCGACCAAAGUGUAUGAUGAUAUGGCAUUCCGGUACCUGUCCUGGAUCCUCUUCCCGCUCCUGGGCUGCUAUGCCGUCUACAGUCUUCUGUACCUGGAGCACAAGGGCUGGUACUCCUGGGUGCUCAGCAUGCUCUACGGCUUCCUGCUGACCUUCGGCUUCAUCACCAUGACGCCCCAGCUCUUCAUCAACUACAAGCUCAAGUCUGUGGCCCACCUUCCCUGGCGCAUGCUCACCUACAAGGCCCUCAACACAUUCAUCGACGACCUGUUCGCCUUUGUCAUCAAGAUGCCCGUUAUGUACCGGAUCGGCUGCCUGCGGGACGAUGUGGUUUUCUUCAUCUACCUCUACCAACGGUGGAUCUACCGCGUCGACCCCACCCGAGUCAACGAGUUUGGCAUGAGUGGAGAAGACCCCACAGCUGCCGCCCCCGUGGCCGAGGUUCCCACAGCAGCAGGGGCCCUCACGCCCACACCUGCACCCACCACGACCACCGCCACCAGGGAGGAGGCCUCCACGUCCCUGCCCACCAAGCCCACCCAGGGGGCCAGCUCUGCCAGCGAGCCCCAGGAAGCCCCUCCAAAGCCAGCAGAGGACAAGAAAAAGGAUUAGUCGAGACUGGUCCUCACCUGCUCCGGCUCCUGGCGACCACUACCCCUGCGUCCCGGCCCCCUCGCCUCCCCUCCCUGUCGCCCUUUCCCUGGACAGAUCAGGCCGGGGCGGUGGGAGGCCCGCCUCAGGUCAGGGCCCAGCGUGUGAUGUAGGGGCCGGGGCAGGCCAGGGUUUGUUUGUGGAGGCGCUGUCUGUCCCUCUGUCCCUCUGUGUUUCCAGCCAUCUCGCCCUGCCAGCCCAGCACCACUGGGAAUCAUGGUGAAGCUGAUGCAGCGUUGCCGAGGGGGUGGGUUGGGCGGGGGUGGGGCCGGGCCCCCCUACGGGAUGCCCACGGCCGUUCAUCAUCUUGUCCCUCGUCCCCCUACCACACUCCCCCUCCUAGACCGCCGCCCUUUAACACAGUCUGGAUUUAAUAAAUUCAUAUGGGUGUUUAACUUAAACUCA